ACACUAUGGCAGGUGGCAGUCCAGCAGCCAAGAGGGUAGUGGUGUACCGGAAUGGGGACCCAUUCUUCCCAGGCUCCCAGCUGGUGGUGACUCAACGCCGCUUCCCCACCAUGGAGGCCUUCCUCUGCGAGGUGACAUCAGCUGUGCAGGCCCCACUGGCUGUGCGUGCCCUCUACACACCUUGUCAUGGCCACCCUGUCACCAACCUGGCAGACUUGAAGAACAGAGGGCAGUAUGUGGCCGCUGGAUUUGAACGAUUCCACAAGCUCCACUAUUUACCCCAUAGAGGGAAGGACCCAGGUGGGAAGAGCUGCAGACUACAAGGUCCUCCCGUGACUCGCCACUUGUGUGAUGGGGCCAUUGGACGGCAGCUGCCUGCAGGUGCUCCCAGCUAUAUCCAUGUGUUCAGGAAUGGGGACCUGGUAAGUCCCCCAUUUAGUCUGAAGCUGUCCCAGGCUGCCAGCCAGGACUGGGAAACUGUGUUGAAGCUCCUGACUGAGAAGGUCAAGUUGCAGAGUGGGGCUGUGUGCAAACUCUGCACCCUAGAGGGGCUCCCACUGUCAGCAGGGAAGGAGCUGGUAACUGGCCAUUACUAUGUGGCUGUCGGAGAGGAUGAGUUCAAGGACCUUCCCUAUCUGGAGCUGCUGGUGCCCAGCCCCUCCCUGCCCAGGGGCUGCUGGCAACCUCCAGGCUCGAAGUCUAGGCCCCACAGGCAGGGGGCCCAAGGCCACAGGGCCCAGGUAACCCAGCCCUCUCCAAAGGAACCAGACCGAAUUAAGCCAUCUGCUUUCUAUGCCAGACCCCAGCAGACCAUUCAGCCAAGAAGCAAGCUCCCCACACUCUCAUUCCCAUCAGGAGUUAUAGGAGUAUAUGGAGCUCCCCACCGAAGGAAGGAGACAGCGGGGGCCCUGGAAGUAGCAGAUGAUGAAGACACUCAGACAGAGGAGCCCUUGGAUCAGAGGGCAGCACAGAUAGUGGAAGAGGCCUUGUCCCUGGAAAACCAGCCUGGGGCUGGGGCUGCUAUCUCAGCCUCAGCCCCAGCUCUGCCAUCUUGAGAGCCAGCAGCUCCAGAGGGCAACUGGGGACCACUACUCUGGCCACCUUUUGUCCUUAGCCUCCAGCAGCUUGUUCCUCAGGAGCCAGCACCUCCGCUGGGCUCACAGGGUACACUGCGGCCUCCUCAGCCCUCCCCGUUCUCCUGCUCCUAAACCCACAGCCCAGCCUUCCCUUCCUCUGAGCAGAGCAGCCCUGGCUGUGGGGGCUAUUUCCUUAUGGGAUUCUCUGGCCAGAGAAAGGAGUAGCUGACUAAGCCUGGGAGAGGGUUUGUCACAAUAAAAGAAUACUUACUAA